GCGGGCGCUGCGCGUGCCGGGCGGAGAAGCGGCGCGAGCCGGGCGCUGCGAACGUUCGCCGCGGGGGUGGCUCCGGGGCCUGAGUAGGCGCUGCCGCUGCCUCAGCCGAGGGGGCUGGGCCGGAGCGUGCGGAGGAGUGAGGCCGCAGGAGACCUUCCCGACGACCCCUGCUCCGGCGGGGAAGUGAGCAAGGAUGAUUGAGGAAAGUGGGAACAAGCGGAAGACCAUGGCAGAGAAGAGGCAGCUGUUCAUAGAAAUGCGUGCUCAGAAUUUUGAUGUCAUACGACUAUCAACUUACAGAACAGCCUGCAAAUUACGAUUUGUACAAAAACGAUGCAACCUUCAUCUUGUUGAUAUCUGGAACAUGAUUGAAGCCUUCCGAGACAAUGGCCUUAAUACACUGGACCAUACCACCGAGAUCAGUGUGUCCCGCCUCGAAACUGUCAUCUCCUCCAUCUACUAUCAGUUGAACAAGCGCCUUCCUUCUACUCACCAAAUUAGUGUGGAACAAUCUAUCAGCCUCCUCCUCAACUUUAUGAUUGCUGCAUAUGACAGUGAGGGCCGAGGCAAGUUGACGGUAUUUUCAGUUAAAGCUAUGUUAGCAACCAUGUGUGGUGGAAAAAUGCUGGACAAAUUGAGAUAUGUUUUCUCCCAGAUGUCAGAUUCCAAUGGCUUAAUGAUAUUUAGCAAGUUUGACCAGUUUCUGAAGGAAGUUCUGAAGCUCCCAACAGCUGUCUUUGAAGGGCCAUCUUUUGGUUACACAGAGCACUCAGUCCGCACCUGUUUUCCACAGCAGAGAAAGAUAAUGCUAAAUAUGUUUUUAGACACAAUGAUGGCUGACCCUCCUCCCCAGUGCCUUGUCUGGCUACCUCUCAUGCACAGGCUUGCCCAUGUUGAGAAUGUCUUCCAUCCCGUGGAGUGCUCCUACUGCCGAUGUGAGAGUAUGAUGGGUUUCCGGUACCGAUGCCAGCAGUGCCACAACUAUCAGCUCUGCCAGAAUUGCUUUUGGCGUGGCCAUGCCGGCGGCCCUCACAGCAACCAGCACCAGAUGAAGGAGCAUUCCUCUUGGAAAUCUCCUGCAAAGAAGCUGAGCCAUGCAAUUAGUAAAUCUUUGGGGUGUGUACCCACGAGAGAACCCCCGCAUCCUGUUUUUCCUGAGCAACCAGAGAAACCACUUGACCUUGCACAUAUAGUUCCUCCUCGCCCUCUGACUAAUAUGAAUGACACCAUGGUUAGCCACAUGUCCUCUGGAGUGCCCACUCCCACCAAGAGUAGAGAUUGGGUUUCACCAUGUUGGCCAAGCUGGUCUCAAACUCCUGAUCUCAAGUGAUCCAACUGCCUCAGACUCCCAAAGUGCUGGAUUACGGGCACGAGCCACCAUACCUGGCCUUGUUUUCAAUUUUUUAUCUCUAAAAUGGGGACAAAAAUAAUAUCUACCUUUUGGGGUUUAUGUGAGAAUUUAAUGUAUUAUUUUUAUGACUUAGGAAAUAAACUGGAAUGUGAGAAUAAGUGAGGAAGAGACAGAAUAAUUUACCAGCAAUGCCCUCUCAAGCAGGAAAGGAAUUUUUAUGGACGAAUACAAAGCAAUUAAGCCUGUCCCACCUACCUAGAUAUUACGAUAACCCUUGCUGUCCUUGGACUUCAGUUUUUUAUGUUUAACACCCAUAGCAUUCAAACCCAGACUCCAGAUCAAAGAUGUUUCCGUUUCAAAACCAGGCAGAUAAGGUGGCCGAUUCAAAGAAUUCAGGUCAUAGUUUUCCUGUUAAUUAUAAGAAUACCAUCUCAUUCAGUAGCAUUUCCCAUCUGAAUUCUUCUCAUCAUUUACUAGUUCUGUCACGCUAAGUCACCCGAGUACAUGAGGGCGACCACAGCUGAAUGUGGCUGCUAGAGGCUAUUAGAAGGAGCAUGGCUUUCUGGACAGUGUUUUAUUGCUUGAAAAAACUAAAAGAAGGGAGCAGUAAUAAUCAUAGCCACCUCUGUAGAGGCCUACCCCUCAGGCUUGCUGUGUUACACCUGCAGGCUUUAUUGUAAGUAGCCAGCUGUGAUUGCCAGUCACAAAAUGAUACCUGUCAUUUUUGAAAGCUGCUUCAGAUAAUCUAUAGCCUGGAUUAAGAUUUCAUCUUAAAGUCAGUGUUUAGCCACUCUUUCUGGUGGAAUUAGCCCACCCUAGAGGUGGUUAUCGUAAACUUUGCAAGGGCUGACCAGCAGACCAAAGGCAGCCAGAGGGCAGACCAGAGAAGAAGGUUGAGCUCCGAUUGAUUAAGAAGCACAAUUACUUGAGUAGCGGCUCCAUAGGAACAAAAUGCUCCUACCCUACCAUUACAGCCCCCAGGAUUUUAGGGGAUUCCAUUUAUAUUCAGUAUGAGAUUGUGAUAUACCAUGUGGAUACUAAUUACCUAAUUCAUAGACUUGGCUUUUCAUGGCCCCAGUAAUCAAAUAGUAUAAAUUUCCAGGUAGUAUUCUACUUGUUUCCUUAAUGACUCCUCAGCUUUUCUUCCCUCCUCUGAAUGUGGACAGACCUGUGUGGCCAGAGAGUCUAACGGAAGCCAGGAGCCCAGCACGUCUUGCCAGCCACAGAGCCUUACUCUGCCCAGACAGGAAUGCUCGCGGAGAUAGAGCAGCUACUCUCCAGAAUAAGAGGUUACAGUAUAGCCAGGAUAUACCCAGUCACUUGGCCGAUGAGCAUGCGCUGAUAGCCUCCUAUGUGGCCCGUCUGCAGCACUGUGCACGUGUUCUGGACAGUCCUAGCCGACUGGAUGAGGAACACCGUCUUAUAGCUCGCUAUGCUGCCCGGCUGGCUGCAGAAGCAGGAAACGUGACUCGUCCUCCCACUGACUUGAGCUUUAACUUUGAUGCCAACAAACAACAAAGACAGCUUAUUGCAGAACUGGAAAACAAAAACAGAGAGAUCCUGCAGGAGAUUCAGCGUCUCCGCCUGGAACACGAGCAGGCCUCCCAGCCCACCCCUGAGAAGGCACAGCAGAACCCCACGCUGCUGGCAGAGCUGCGGCUGCUGAGGCAAAGGAAGGAUGAACUGGAGCAGAGGAUGUCGGCCCUGCAGGAGAGCAGGCGGGAGCUGAUGGUCCAGCUGGAAGAGCUGAUGAAGUUGCUGAAGGCUCAGGCCACAGGGUCACCACAUACAUCGCCCACCCAUGGAGGCGGCCGGCCAAUGCCCAUGCCAGUGCGCUCCACGUCUGCCGGCUCCACCCCCACCCACUGUCCGCAGGACUCGCUGAGCGGAGUCGGGGGAGACGUGCAGGAGGCCUUCGCACAAGGUACGAGGAGAAACCUCCGCAAUGACCUGCUGGUGGCAGCUGACUCCAUCACCAACACCAUGUCAUCCCUGGUGAAGGAGCUCCAUUCAGCAGAGGAAGGUGCAGAGGAAGAAGAAGAGAAGAUGCAGAAUGGGAAAGACAGAGGUUAGCAGAGGAGCCGGACACAGAGGAAGCUCAGGCACAGAGGACGAGGAGCAAGCUGGCGCCGACAUGGCGAAGGCAAGGUCUUCCCCCAGAGGCACAUUCCUCUCCAUCUUUCCACCGCACACCUGGACCAGGCUUGCAGGCUGCCAGACGUCACUCCACCCGCCAGGGAGAGGGGAGCCAGAGCCGGUGGGAAGCGGGGAGGGGCUGCGUGGCACAGCUAGUGGGCCUCCCCCUGCACAGCCCUGCAUGUACUAGCACCUUCAUCACUCCCCUCAGGGCAUGGUCUCAUCUCCGCAUCAGGAAUUCACCUGGAGGUUGAAAAGAGAAAAGAAAAAGCACCAA